GCGGUUUGAGUGUUCAGAGAUUGGUUGUGCUACUGAAGGCGGCGGACGUGGGACCCCCGGUUCCGUCUCGGGAAGUAACUCAUCUGCCCCCUCUUUGAACACCUCCGCUCACGAGCGCAGCACGUGGAAACCGUCAGUGAUUUGUGUCUGCAACGUGUGUGAGAGAAUGGAGGUGUGUGACACGGUAUAUUCUCCUGCUCUCGGCGGCCCAGCCCUCGUGACUCUCCGGUCUCUGUUUCACCUCCCCCACCCCUUUCUCCUCCAAGUUGGGUGCCUCCUGCCCUGCUGGGUGAGGAGGGUGGGGAUUGCAACCGAGAACACCGCGUCCUUUCUGGCUCCCGCUGGGGCGGCUCCUCCAUCCCUUUUCUUACAUAACCUACCACGCACGUUACCAGCUCAGAUGCCAGCCCGCCACGACGCUAGAGGUCAAAACGAAACUCAGUUUUUCCUGACUUUUUUAUCCAGGCUUCUCGGGCCCGGCGUCCUAAAUUAUCUGAUUCCAAGCACGGGGAACAGAAUGGGAUUCAAACAGGAUCUACCCCCUCUGCAGCCCUUCAAGAAGAGGUAUGAUUGCUACCACUUUUCCCCACAAAGUGACGAAAGGAAACAGCGACGGAAGCGCAACCGAACCCUGGAAUUGGUGUCUCGACUGGUCCAUUCCCGGCCCACCCCCAUUAACCGGCUCGAGCCACUCCCAGGACGAAGUCAAGGCCUCGGAAGGCGACUACAACUCCCAGCAGGUCGAGCAGCUCCGCCCGCGCUGAUUCUCCAUUGGCCUUCCGGGGGUGGGGAUUAG